AUGCGGCGGCGUGGUGAAAUAGAUAUGGCGACCGAGGGGGAUGUGGAGCUGGAGUUGGAGACUGAGACCAGUGGACCAGAGCGGCCUCCGGAGAAGCCACGGAAACAUGACAGCGGUGCGGCGGACUUGGAGCGGGUCACCGACUAUGCAGAGGAGAAGGAGAUCCAGAGUUCCAAUCUGGAGACGGCCAUGUCUGUGAUUGGAGACAGAAGGUCCCGGGAGCAGAAAGCCAAACAGGAGCGGGAGAAAGAACUGGCAAAAGUCACUAUCAAGAAGGAAGAUCUGGAGCUAAUAAUGACUGAGAUGGAGAUAUCUCGAGCAGCAGCAGAACGCAGUUUGCGGGAACACAUGGGCAACGUGGUAGAGGCGCUUAUUGCCCUAACCAACUGAUGCGUGCUUUCUCAAAUAUACCUACUGGAUUAAUUUAUGGCAAUAAAAUUUUUUUUUGUCUUUUUCAGUUUUAUCAUCUUGGGUCAAGUAGAGUGUAUACUAUAUCCUAUGUUGUGGAGAAUUUAUAUGUUGGAGACUAACUGAAUUUAAGUGACCCAUUAAAAUCUAGCACACCUGUAUGAAAAAUCAGUGUAGAAGAAUACCUCAUGUGCAGAUGCUAGGUGGCAGGCCAGUCUCAUUCAUCUGACUAGCUCUCAACAGUAUUCAAGGUACAUCUGGAGUCUCAGCAGAGUUACUGUACUCAAAUGGCAUGUGUCUCCAAGACAGCUUAUGAAUAUCUAAAAGGCCAGCUACCUGCCUAGGAGCCACUAUAUAUAUAGAUAGAUGUAGGUUAUGAACCCAGUUCAUAGGCCACCUUGAGUUAGAAUUUUGGUACCUACAACAUGCUUGAUUUUGAGUGAUUAAAAAAAAAUAAUUUGGCUGGGUGCUGUGGCUCACACCUCUAAUCCCAGCACUUUGGGAGGUCGAGGCAGGUAGAUCACGAGGUCAGGAAUUCAAGACCAGCCUGGCCAACAUGUGAAACCCCGUCUCCACUGAAAAUAGAAAAAUUAGCUGGGCAUGGUGGUGGGCGCCUAUAAUCCCAGCUAUUCUGGAGGCUGAGGCAGGAAUCGCUUGAAAUUGGAAAGCAGAGGUUGCAGUGAGCUGAGAUCACACUACUGUACUACUGUACUCCAGCCUGGGGGAAAGAGUGAAACUCCAUCUCAAAAAAAAAAAAAAAAAAAAAAGCCCGGGCACAGUGGCUCACACCUGUAAUCCCAGCACUUUGGGAGGCUGAGGCAGUCGGAUCAUGAGGUCAGGAGUUGAAGACAAGCCUGGCCAACAUGGUGAAACCCUGUCUCUACUAAAAAUACAAAAAAAAUAAAAUUAGCCAGGCGUGGUGGUGCAUGCCUGUAGUCCCAGCUACUCAGGAGGCUGAAGCAGAAGAAUUGCUUGAACCAGGGAGGCGGAAGUUGCAGUGAGCUGAGAUUGUGCCACUGUACUCCAGCCUGGGUGACAGAGCGAGACUGUCUCAAAAACAAAACAACAAAAAAGAAUUUAGGGGCCAGGCAUGGUGGCUCAUGCCUGUAAUCCCAACACCUUGGGAAGCUGAGGCAAGACGAUCACUUGAGCCCAGCAGUUUGAGACCAGCUUGGGCAACACAGUGAGAUUUCGUCUCUACCGCGCUCCCCCCACCACCAAAAAAAGAAUUUAGGUACCUGAGGGUUAGAACAUGGUAAGACUAGAAGAUAUCAAAGGUUGGGCCAGGUGUGGUGACUCAUGCCUGUAACCCCAGCACUUUGGGGAGGCUGGGCUGGGAGGACUGUGUCAGGUCAGGAUUUCCAGACCAGCCUGGGCAACAUAGCAUGACCUUGUCUCUACUAAAAUUAAAAAAAAAAAAAGCCAGGCAUGGUGGCAUGUGCCUGUCUGUGGUCCCAGAUACUCUGGAGGCUGAGAUGGAUUUGCUUGAGCCUGGGAGGUUGAGGCUGCAGUGAGCUGAGAUUGUGCUACUGCACUCCAGCCUGGGCGACAGAGCAAGACUGUCUCAAAACGAAAAAAACCUAUGAAAGGUUUUGAUUGGUAUUCAAAUUCUAAGCCAUAAUACAUUCUACAUGCCAUUUCCUAUCCUAGAGAGAAGGUAAUUUUACUUUAAAGGUUAAUCAGGGCCGGGCGUGGUGGCGCAUGCCUAUAAUCCCAGCACUCUGGGAGGCCGAGGCAGGUGGAUCACCUGGGAUCAGGAGUUUGAGACGAGCCUGGCCAAAAUGGUGAAACCCCAUCUCUACUAAAAGUACAAAAAAAAAUUAGCUGGGUGUGGUGGUGGACGCCUGUAAUUCCAGCUACUAGGGAGGCUGAGGCAGGAGAAUCUCUUGAACCCAGGAGGUUGCAGUGAGCAGAGAUCGCGCCACUGCACUCCAGACUGGGCAACAAGAGUGAAACUCCAUCUCAAAAAAAAAAAAAAAAAAAAUCAGCUUGGACCAACUCACACAUGUUGAACUAGUUUCCUCAACUAUAAAACUGUGACGGCCCCAGCUAGGCACAGUGGCUCAACGCCUGUAAUCUCAGCACUUUGGGAGGCUGAGGCGGGCGGAUCGCGAAGUGAAGAUCAAGACCAUCCUGGCUAACAUGGUGAAACCCCGUCUCUACUAAAAAUACAAAAAUUAGCCAGGCAUGGUGGCAGGCGCCUGUAGUCCCAGCUACUCGGGAGGCUGAGGCACUCUAGCCUGGGCAACAGAGCCGUCUCUUUAAAACAAACAAACAAACAAAAAAAAAACCCUGCAACGGCCCCUGAGUCUGCUGUAAGGACACUCAAAUGGCAAUUACAGACAUUUCUCCAAGAGUUUCAAGGCCUUACCCUCAUUCUGACUCUAGGAUAAUUCUUAGAUUGUAUCCCACACAACAGUGACUUGUACCUGUGUUCAUCUUUAUGUAUUUACCACCUCAUAGUAAUUAUUUGCAUUCAUUUUUAUCGUACGACACUAAACUAUUUGAUUCUUCCAGUGGGACAUUUAAAGGAUGUGAGAAGACCUUGGUCUUCUCAAAAACAUCUGUAUUUGGUCAUGGAAUAAAUCCAGAUGCUACCUAAA